AGUCCCAGCUCAGAGCCGCAACCUGCACAGCCAUGCCCGGGCAAGAACUCAGGACGGUGAAUGGCUCUCAGAUGCUCCUGGUGUUGCUGGUGCUCUCGUGGCUGCCGCAUGGGGGCGCCCUGUCUCUGGCCGAGGCGAGCCGCGCAAGUUUCCCGGGACCCUCAGAGUUGCACUCCGAAGACUCCAGAUUCCGAGAGUUGCGGAAACGCUACGAGGACCUGCUAACCAGGCUGCGGGCCAACCAGAGCUGGGAAGAUUCGAACACCGACCUCGUCCCGGCCCCUGCAGUCCGGAUACUCACGCCAGAAGUGCGGCUGGGAUCCGGCGGCCACCUGCACCUGCGUAUCUCUCGGGCCGCCCUUCCCGAGGGGCUCCCCGAGGCCUCCCGCCUUCACCGGGCUCUGUUCCGGCUGUCCCCGACGGCGUCAAGGUCGUGGGACGUGACACGACCGCUGCGGCGUCAGCUCAGCCUUGCAAGACCCCAGGCGCCCGCGCUGCACCUGCGACUGUCGCCGCCGCCGUCGCAGUCGGACCAACUGCUGGCAGAAUCUUCGUCCGCACGGCCCCAGCUGGAGUUGCACUUGCGGCCGCAAGCCGCCAGGGGGCGCCGCAGAGCGCGUGCGCGCAACGGGGACCACUGUCCGCUCGGGCCCGGGCGUUGCUGCCGUCUGCACACGGUCCGCGCGUCGCUGGAAGACCUGGGCUGGGCCGAUUGGGUGCUGUCGCCACGGGAGGUGCAAGUGACCAUGUGCAUCGGCGCGUGCCCGAGCCAGUUCCGGGCGGCAAACAUGCACGCGCAGAUCAAGACGAGCCUGCACCGCCUGAAGCCCGACACGGUGCCAGCGCCCUGCUGCGUGCCCGCCAGCUACAAUCCCAUGGUGCUCAUUCAAAAGACCGACACCGGGGUGUCGCUCCAGACCUAUGAUGACUUGUUAGCCAAAGACUGCCACUGCAUAUGAGCAGUCCUGGUCCUUCCACUGUGCACCUGCGCGGAGGACGCGACCUCAGUUGUCCUGCCCUGUGGAAUGGGCUCAAGGUUCCUGAGACACCCGAUUCCUGCCCAAACAGCUGUAUUUAUAUAAGUCUGUUAUUUAUUAUUAAUUUAUUGGGGUGACCUUCUUGGGGACUCGGGGGCUGGUCUGAUGGAACUGUGUAUUUAUUUAAAACUCUGGUGAUAAAAAUAAAGCUGUCUGAACUGUU